GGUCUCAUUCUACAAAGAGAGAGGUGGCCCCCCUUUCUUGACCUCCUCCUCCUUCAAGCUCAAACACCACCUCCCUUAUUCAGGACCGGCACUUCUUAAUGUUUGUGGCUUUCUCUCCAGCCUCUCUUAGGAGGGGUAAUGGUGGAGUUGGCAUCUUGUAACUCUCCUUUCUCCUUUCUUCCCCUUUCUCUGCCCGCCUUUCCCAUCCUGCUGUAGACUUCUUGAUUGUCAGUCUGUGUCACAUCCAGUGAUUGUUUUGGUUUCUGUUCCCUUUCUGACUGCCCAAGGGGCUCAGAACCCCAGCAAUCCCUUCCUUUCACUACCUUCUUUUUUGGGGGUAGUUGGAAGGGACUGAAAUUGUGGGGGGAAGGUAGGAGGCACAUCAAUAAAGAGGAAACCACCAAGCUGAACUGAAUUUUGCCUUGUGUUGCUCCCCUCGUCCCGCUGAUUUUAAGUCUUUCCAAGGUGUCAGUGGGUUUCAGUGGUGGGGAAAGAAGAGUACUGGGUACAAGCUGGAGGGAUAGAAGUAUAUUUUGGUUUAUUCUGUUCAUGUUGGGCUUUUCCCUGUCUGCAAAAAGAGGGUGCUUUUGUUGUGAUGGAAUGGAAUACUGAGGAUUAUUUCUUGAAACUUUAGUUUUAUAACACGCAUGUGAAACUAAAUGUUAAAAAUGCUCAUGUAAAAAAAAAUUUUUUUUUACUGUGGGUUCCUGUGGAGAAAGUUCCGAAGUACCUGCUUUAGGUGAACAUCCACAUUUGCUAGAACAUUCUAACUAAGAUAUUUUCAUGUGUGCAAGCUAGUAAAACGGCUGUUCUCAGUUGCAUGUCACUUGGCUAGACUUUUGCCGGUGUGUGGGAUCCGGCAGAGUGGAAUCAGGGAGGGAGAAGACUGGGAGCGGGAGCCAUUAUCGCCAGGAAUACUUCAACUCCCAGCAAUCAUUUCUCCGGCAGGCCGGAAGUGGGGCGGUCCUCCUGGGGAGAAAGAAGCUGCAGAACGAGGCAGUAUGGUGGCCGAGAGUUCUAAUCCCUUCUUCCUCUUCUUUCUUGGUCCCGCCCAGCCUACAUCUCCCAGGGGCCUGCGCGCGCACUUCCGCUCUCCCCUCCGGCUCCUGGUCUCCCCGCCGCUCCCCGGGGGAGGGGAGCGGCUUGGUGCGCCUGCGCCAGCCUGUGGCUUUCUGGGAAUCAAAGUUCCGGAGGUUCAUGCGGUCCCUUUUCCGCUGUUCCCGGACGGACUACAAAACCCUUGAUCCACCUCCGACCCUUAAGCCAGAGACUCAGCCACCAGAGAAACGGCGGAGAACAAUUGAGGAUUUCAACAAAUUCUGCAGUUUUGUUUUGGCAUAUGCUGGUUACAUUCCCCCUAGCAAAGAGGAAAGUGACUGGCCAGCCUCUGGCUCCAGCUCUCCAUUGCGAGGAGAGAGUGCGGCCGACAGUGAUGGCUGGGACUCGGCCCCCUCAGAUCUUCGAACCAUCCAGACUUUUGUUAAGAAAGCAAAGUCAUCCAAGAGAAGGGCAGCUCAAGCAGGUCCCACCCAGCCAGGACCCCCAAGGUCCACUUUCUCUCGUCUGCAGGCCCCCGACAGUGCUACCUUGCUUGAGAAGAUGAAGCUCAAGGACUCUCUCUUUGAUCUGGAUGGGCCCAAAGUGGCAUCUCCUUUGUCCCCCACAUCCCUGACACAUACCUCCCGGCCCCCUGCUGCUCUUACCCCCGUGCCCCUUUCCCAGGGGGACCUCUCCCAUCCUCCUCGAAAGAAGGACCGAAAGAACCGAAAGUUGGGGCCAGGAGCUGGGGCUGGCUUUGGGGUGCUUCGGAGGCCUCGGCCAACUCCUGGGGAUGGGGAAAAGAGAUCUCGAAUCAAGAAGAGCAAGAAGCGGAAGUUAAAAAAGGCAGAACGGGGGGAUAGACUCCCACCUCCUGGGCCUCCCCAGGCACCCCCCAGUGAUACAGACUCUGAAGAGGAGGAGGAAGAGGAGGAAGAGGAAGAAGAAGAAGAGAUGGCAACAGUGGUAGGGGGUGAAGCCCCAGUCCCUGUGCUGCCAACACCCCCUGAGGCUCCUAGGCCCCCUGCCACAGUGCACCCUGAAGGAGUCCCUCCUGCUGACAGUGAAAGCAAGGAGGUGGGCAGCACUGAAACAAGCCAAGAUGGAGAUGCCAGCUCCAGUGAAGGCGAGAUGCGGGUCAUGGACGAGGACAUCAUGGUAGAAUCAGGUGAUGACUCAUGGGAUCUGAUCACAUGUUACUGUCGAAAGCCCUUUGCAGGGCGGCCCAUGAUUGAGUGCAGCCUGUGUGGGACGUGGAUCCACCUCUCCUGUGCUAAGAUUAAGAAGACCAACGUCCCCGACUUCUUUUAUUGCCAGAAAUGCAAGGAACUGAGGCCAGAGGCCCGGCGGUUAGGGGGGCCUCCCAAAUCUGGAGAGCCCUGAUGGCACCAACUUUAGCCUGGAACUUCCAAAUGACAACAUGAUUUGGGAACUGAGCCUCAGGGUCCUCAGCCUAUCCCCUGGAGCUUGGAUACUGUCUGCACUUCAAGGCAGGAAUUCUCAAGGGAGACUUGUUUGAAAAUGAGUGUCUCACUUUCCCACCCUAUCCUUCCUCCCCACUCUGUGGACUUGAAAUUGAAUCCAUUACGGUUGGGGAUGGGAGGCUGUCUGUGUCCCGACACAUAAUCUCUGUCUCUUGGACCUGCCACCAUCACUUUCUGGGUCAGGAUUGGAAUUGGGAUGGAAUGGGACAGUUGUCUAUAAAACUCUAGUGUAAAUAUUAGCACUCCCCUCCCUCAUCUUUUCUUCUAUUUCACUCCCCAUUUAUUUUCUUCUACACCGGUUGUAUUUUUAAUUUUGGACUUCCCCUAUUGGGCAUGGCAGCUCAAAGGUGGAGUACUAGAGCCUGGCCAAGUGAGGAAGGAAAGCAGAAAGGUGACGAUUCUCACUCACCUCUUUUGUUUUUAAUAAUAUCGGCCGCUGUUUGUACAGACAGCCUGCGUGUUGUAAAUAAAGCAGAGUGGGCUCUUU